ACUGAGUGCUUCGCAGCUGUCUGGGCGAGAGGCACAGCGAUGGGCUCCGUGCUGAGCACCGACAGCGGCAAAUCGGCGCCCGCCUCUGCCACCGCGCGGGCCCUGGAGCGCAGGAGGGACCCGGAGUUGCCCGUCACGUCCUUCGACUGCGCCGUGUGCCUUGAGGUGUUACACCAGCCUGUCCGGACCCGCUGUGGCCACGUAUUCUGCCGUUCCUGUAUUGCUACCAGUCUAAAGAACAACAAGUGGACCUGUCCUUAUUGCCGGGCAUAUCUUCCUUCAGAAGGAGUUCCAGCAACUGAUGUAGCCAAAAGAAUGAAAUCAGAGUAUAAGAACUGCGCUGAGUGUGACACCCUGGUUUGCCUCAGUGAAAUGAGGGCACAUAUUCGGACUUGUCAGAAGUACAUAGAUAAGUAUGGACCACUACAAGAACUUGAGGAGACAGCAGCAAGGUGUGUAUGUCCCUUUUGUCAGAGGGAACUGUAUGAAGACAGCUUGCUGGAUCAUUGUAUUACUCAUCACAGAUCGGAACGGAGGCCUGUGUUCUGUCCACUUUGCCGUUUAAUACCCGAUGAGAAUCCAAGCAGCUUCAGUGGCAGUUUAAUAAGACAUCUGCAAGUUAGUCACACUUUGUUUUAUGAUGAUUUCAUAGAUUUUAAUAUAAUUGAGGAAGCUCUUAUCCGAAGAGUCUUAGACCGGUCACUUCUUGAAUAUGUGAAUCACUCGAACACCACAUAAUUUUAUUAAAACGAAGGGAAAAGGGACCACUGAAUUGCACCAUUUAAGAUGCUGCUUGAACAAAUGGGAGGGAAGUUGUCAAUGAUUGAUGGGCAAAAAUGUACAACACAGUUAUGUGUUUGUCCAUGUUUAUUGUUAUAGUGCAUUUAAAAACUGCUUUAAUUUUAAUGGUUUAAAUCUGUUUUACAUCCUUGAGAUUCUUACACAUCUAACAACAAAAAAAAUUAUCUACAUCAGUCAUUGUUACAUGGAAAAGACAGGUGGUAGGCAAGUAGGUGGAGGAUCUCGGUUUGCAAAUUAGAUAAUACUCUGUGUAUAAUGCUACAUAUCAAUAACUACCAUCAUGGUUAGGCACGAUAACUAAUCUUUGUUCUGUGUAAAAAAAUAUGGAGAGUGAAACAAAGUGCAGACAUUCAAAGAAAUAAGAAAUCUGCUCCAAUGCUCUUGUUCUAAUCUCUAAUAGGUUAACGUUAAUAAUCUUGUAUGGGAGUUGGAAAGGAAAAUUUUGGAAGUCAAGAAAGUCCAUUUAGGCCGGACGCGGUGGCUUACGCUUGUAAUCCCAGCACUUUGGGAGGCUGAAGCAGGCGGAUCACAAGGUCAGGAGUUCGAGACCAGCCUGGCCAACACUGGUCUCUGUGAAACUCCGUCUCUACUAAAAAUACAAAAAUUAGCUGGACGUGUUGGCGGGCAUCUGUAAUACCAGCUACUUGGGAGGCUGAGGCAGAAGAAUCACUUGAACCCGGGAGGCAGAGGUUACAGUGAGCUGAGAUCGCACCAGUACACUCCAGCCUGGGUAACAGAGCUAGACUCCAUCUCAAAAAAAAAAAAAAAAAAAAUCCAUUUAACCAAAUUGUCUUACAUAAUACUGUAACAAAACAAAUUUUGUGUUAGAAAAGUAUACUUAAUUCUUUGACUUUUUAUAACUGCAUACAUAAGAAUUCAAUAUUUUUCAAAUAUUUAUAGCUUAUUUAGAAAUAUUUCUAUAAUAUAAGCAAUUUCUUAAAAACCAUCAGAUGAUACUUACAGUAUAAGUAUUCACAUCCAGACUUUUUAGUAGAAAACCCUAAGGGCUUUGAUAUCUUUUUUGAUUGUAACAUUUUAAAAAUUAUGAAAUAAAAGUACUGAAAACCAGACACAAAAUUUAUAGCUGAAUGCCUUAUUAUAAGGAAAUACUCUUUUAGGACUCAGCCAGUCACCCCACGUGUCCUUUUUGUGUCCUGUCACAAUUACAACCCCACAAAAGUAACUGCUAGACUGAUUUAAAUGGUAAUCACUUUGUUGCAUUUGAUUACUGCUGCCACACCUAAAUGCAUAUAUCUAUAUUUUAAUAUUAUCAAUUUAAAGUUGUUAUUAAAUGUAUAUUUUAUUUUACAUCUCUUUUUUAAUCUAGAAGUUCCUCCUUCUUUCCAGUUCCUUAAAAUUUACCUGGUGAAGAACCUGAUCCUAGGACCUAUAGAGUUUCCCAUACUUUGUAUUUUGCUGAUUGCACACUCAUGGCACGGUUCAGCACAUUGCCCUGUCCUCUCGAUAUUAGCACACAGUGCAGGUUCAGGCACAUUGAAUUUGAGAAGACUUAGGUUCAGUCCUUUGGCAAGACUGUAAAUCACGGUGUCUUUCUUUCCUUCCUCCUUCUUCUCUCUCUCUCUCUCUCUCUCUUUCCUUUUCUUUCUCUUUUUUUCAGAGUUGCACUCUGUUGCCCAGGCUGGAGUACAGUGGCACGAUCUCGACUCACUGCAACCUCCAUCUCCCGGGUUCAAGCAGUUCUCCUGUUUCAGCCUCCCAAGUAGCUGGGACUACAGGUGCACGCCACCAUGCCCGGCUAAUUUUUGUAUUUUUAGUAGAGGGGUUUCACCAUAAUGGUCAGGCUGGUCUUGAACUCCUGAACUCAAGUGAUCCACCAGCCUUGGCCUCCCAAAAUGCUGGGAUUACAGGCAUGAGCCACCAUGCCCAGCUAAUUUUUGUAUUUUUAGUAGAGACAGGGUUUCACCAUAAUAGCCAGGCUGGUCUCAAACUCCUUACCUUGUGAUCCGCCCACCUCAGCCUUCCAAAGUGCUGGGAUUAUAGGCGUGAGCCACUGUGCCCGGCCUACAGGGUUUUUAUCUAACCUUUCUGUUACAACUGUACCUCUCCUUCUGUACUGAAAGUCCUGGUUUUCAAGAACACAGGGCACGAUAGAAUUAGAACAUCCCACAAUUACUCAUUUCUUUUAUUUAUCUUACACUUACAGCUGUCUCAGAAUAACAAUAGAAAUACAACCACAAAUAAUAUGGCAAUUGAAACAAUUAAAAAGUUUUCAUUUGCUUUUCUCAUUCUUUCCCAAUUUUUUUUUUUUUUUGAGAUGGAGUCUCGCGCUCUUGUUGCCCAGGCUGGAGUGCAAUGGCACGAUCUCGGCUCACUGCAACCUCUGCCUCCUGGAUUCAAGCAAUUCUCCUGCCUCAGCUUCCCGAGUAGCUGGGAUUAUAGGCAUGCGCCACCACGCCCUGCUAAUUUUGUAUUUUUAGUAGAGUCAGGAUUUCUCCACAUUGGUCAGGCUGGCCUCAAACUCUCGACCUCAGGUGAUCCGCCUGCCUCGGCCUCCCAAAGUGCUGGGAUUACAGGUGUGAGCCACUGCGCCCGACAUCCCAAUUUUUAAAAUAGUUAUACUAUGUCAACAUUUUCAGAACAUACUGGUAUAGCAUACUGUACUUUCUUCCUUUUAUCCCCCAUUUAUUCUUAGUUCUUCAACUAUAUAUUUAACACUUGCCCCCAGUUUUGUUUUGUUUUGUUUUGAGGAGGAAUCUUGCUCUGUUGCCCAGGCUGGAGUGCAGUGGUGUGAUCUUGGCUCACUGCAACCUCCGCCUCCCGGGUUCAAGUGAUUCUCCUGCCUCAGCCUCUCGAGUAGCUGGGAUUACAAGUGGGCACCACCACACCCGGCUAAUUGUUGUAUUUUUAGUAGAGAUGGGUUUUGCCAUGUUGGCCAGGCUGGUUUUGAACUCCUGACCUCAAGUGAUCCACCUGUGUUGGCCUCCUAAAGUACUGGGAUUACAGGUGUGUGCCACCGCGCCAGGCAAUUGCCCCCAGUUUUUAUUUGAUGGCUCUGACUGUUUCUCAUAUCUGACUCUUUAAUUAUGAAUCCAGGGCAUAGAUUAGUAUCUCCAUCUUGUAAGGAUGCAAAGAAGCCAUGAAAAUAAGUAAUAUCAACUCCUGAGGAUAAAACGUUACUUGACUAGAGUUAGCUUUUUAAUUGUAAUCAUUUAUAAACUUCUUUGUUCCUUACAUAUAAGCAUAGUCAUAACCAUGGUACCCAAAAUUUUCUAUAAGUUAUUGUAACUCCUUAAAGGUCUUGCUACAGUUCUUUUAUCCAGUACAAAUAAUUGGGAAAAUGUAAAGCUGAAUGAAAUCUAGUGAGCCUCAUAUCCUCCCUUUUAGAUAUUGAUUUUAAGUUUGCUUUUCACAGCUGCUAAAAAGUAACAACUGAUUUUUAGUUCCACAACCUCUCUUUCUUCAAUUUAGAUGGAUCAUACAAUAAAGCAAAAUCUGGCUGGUUACAGUGGCUCACACCUAUAAUCCCAGCACUUUGGGAGGCUGAGGUGGAGGGUCUCAUGAGCCCAGGAGUUCAAGACCAACCUGGGCAAUAUAGUGAGACUCUUUCUAUUUAAACAAAAACAAAAACAAACAAACAAACAAACAAAAAGCUGGGCAUGAUGCACACCUUUAGUUUCAGCUACUAAGGAGGCUGAGGUUGGAGGAUCACUUGAGCCUAGGAGGUCAACACUGCAGUGAGCUAUGAUCAUGCUACUGCCCUCCAGCCUGGGCAACAGAGCAAGACCCUGUCUCCAAAAACAUAAAUAAUUAAAUAUAAAUAAAAAUAAAGCAAAAUCUGUUGGGAAACGAGAAAAAGGAGAGGAAUUUUUCAGGAAUAAUCAUAAAAAGAAAUGAUCAUCAGACUGAAAGUCCAGAGCCUGAGAAAUGAAAACAUAUUUUUAAGCAUUGGUGUUGACCAUGCAGACAAACUUUUGUUAAUUCAGAGCGAUACAAAAGGCACUUUGAAUCUAUAAAACUUGAAAAAGUUAAAAAUUGUAUGUCGGAUAAAGCUUUAAGUCAUCUGUCACUAUUAACCUCAGUGCAGCAAUUCUGACUCCUGUGCCUGGAUUCCUUUUAUGAUAAUUUUGCCACCUACAGGACAGAUUAGGUGCUGGUCGCCUGAAUUAUUUUGUGUUCUGAAUUAUUUUGAGCUCUAAAAUGGUAAAGUACAAAUACUCAUUGUUUUACUGUGCCUUUGGCCUUUUAUAAAAAGGUAUUUAUAAUUCGUUGAUAAAAACCAAUAUUUGAAGCUGUUGAUUACCAACAAAAAAGUUUCACUCUCUUUAUAGUGCUUCAGGAUACAACUUUUUCAGGGCCUUAUUAGAGAAAAACUGAUUCACAUGUUAUUCUUCUAAAGCUAAAUUAUUAAAAUGUAGGUUGAAAGAUUGGAUUGAUUGUGAAUCUACACUAAAGAUAUGGUUCCAGGCAGACCUCCUUAGAGACCUCCAGGCAGACCUCCUUACUGUCUUCAGUGAUGUUUAAUUUCAUUACUGUUACUGGGUGCCAAGUGUCUUUCAUUUGGAAGUGAACUUACUCCAGUUAUUGAAUGUUUAUCAUAUCAUAAUUUGCAUUUUUCCAACAUUGAAGGUAUUUUAAAAAGUCACUAAGAGAUUCAUUCUUUUAUUAUUCAACUACAAAAAAAUAGUGUAAUGAUCAGAAUUUAAAAUGUGUGAUUCUUUUUCUUCUGUAAGUAUGUAUUGCUAUGAUAAAUAAAAAAUGGCAGGACCAUUGUUUUUAUUAAAAUAUCUACUGUGUCUAUUCUUAAACAUUAA